CCUCCUCGCGGCUCACCUUGUCGCUGGAGCAAUCUCAGGAGAUGCUCCAGUGUUUGGGAAGAGGGGUCGCUCCAGGACAGAGGGGCUGUUGUGCACACCCCGUCUGUUGUGACCUCGGACAGCCGUCGGGAUGGAGGUGAGAAGACGGCCGUGACGCGCGCCCGCGGGGCCCCCUGCACCCCCAGCAGCCCACAGCGCUCCCUGCCCCCCUCCCCCGCAGCAGCGGGCCUUGCCGUCGAGUGACAGCGGCCUGGGGGGGCAGGGGGGGCGGGGGCGGCCGGAUCAGCGAUGCCGGCGGGCAUGACGAAGCAUGGCUCCCGCUCCACCAGCUCGCUGCCGCCCGAGCCCAUGGAGAUCGUGCGCAGCAAGGCGUGCUCUCGGCGGGUCCGCCUCAACGUCGGGGGGCUGGCGCACGAGGUACUCUGGCGUACCCUGGACCGCCUGCCCCGCACGCGGCUGGGCAAGCUCCGCGACUGCAACACGCACGACUCGCUGCUCGAGGUGUGCGAUGACUACAGCCUCGACGACAACGAGUACUUCUUUGACCGCCACCCGGGCGCCUUCACCUCCAUCCUCAACUUCUACCGCACUGGGCGACUGCACAUGAUGGAGGAGAUGUGCGCGCUCAGCUUCAGCCAAGAGCUCGACUACUGGGGCAUCGACGAGAUCUACCUGGAGUCCUGCUGCCAGGCCCGCUACCACCAGAAGAAAGAGCAGAUGAACGAGGAGCUCAAGCGUGAGGCCGAGACCCUACGGGAGCGGGAAGGCGAGGAGUUCGAUAACACGUGCUGCGCAGAGAAGAGGAAAAAACUCUGGGACCUACUGGAGAAGCCCAAUUCCUCUGUGGCUGCCAAGAUCCUUGCCAUAAUUUCCAUCAUGUUCAUCGUCCUCUCCACCAUUGCCCUGUCCCUCAACACGCUGCCUGAGCUACAGAGCCUCGAUGAGUUCGGCCAGUCCACAGACAACCCCCAGCUGGCCCACGUGGAGGCCGUGUGCAUCGCAUGGUUCACCAUGGAGUACCUGCUGAGGUUCCUCUCCUCGCCCAAGAAGUGGAAGUUCUUCAAGGGCCCACUCAAUGCCAUUGACUUGUUGGCCAUUCUGCCAUACUAUGUCACCAUUUUCCUCACCGAAUCCAACAAGAGCGUGCUGCAAUUCCAGAAUGUCCGCCGCGUGGUCCAGAUCUUCCGCAUCAUGCGAAUUCUCCGCAUCCUUAAGCUUGCACGCCACUCCACUGGCCUCCAGUCUCUGGGCUUCACUUUGCGGAGGAGCUACAAUGAGUUGGGCUUGCUCAUCCUCUUCCUUGCCAUGGGCAUUAUGAUCUUCUCCAGCCUUGUCUUCUUUGCUGAGAAGGAUGAGGACGACACCAAGUUCAAAAGCAUCCCAGCCUCUUUCUGGUGGGCCACCAUCACCAUGACUACUGUUGGGUAUGGAGACAUCUACCCCAAGACUCUCCUGGGGAAAAUUGUUGGGGGACUCUGCUGCAUUGCAGGAGUCCUGGUGAUUGCUCUUCCCAUCCCCAUCAUCGUCAAUAACUUCUCUGAGUUCUAUAAGGAGCAGAAGAGACAGGAGAAAGCAAUCAAACGGCGAGAGGCUCUGGAGAGAGCCAAGAGGAAUGGCAGCAUCGUAUCCAUGAACAUGAAGGAUGCUUUUGCCCGGAGCAUUGAGAUGAUGGACAUUGUGGUUGAGAAAAAUGGGGAGAAUAUGGGUAAGAAAGACAAAGUACAAGAUAACCACUUGUCUCCUAACAAAUGGAAAUGGACAAAGAGGACACUGUCUGAAACCAGCUCAAGUAAGUCCUUUGAAACCAAGGAACAGGGAUCCCCUGAAAAAGCCAGAUCGUCUUCUAGUCCUCAGCACCUGAACGUUCAGCAGUUGGAAGACAUGUACAAUAAGAUGGCCAAGACCCAAUCCCAACCCAUCCUCAAUACCAAGGAGUCAGCAGCACAGAGCAAACCAAAGGAAGAACUUGAAAUGGAGAGUAUCCCCAGCCCCGUAGCCCCUCUGCCCACUCGCACAGAAGGGGUCAUUGACAUGCGAAGUAUGUCAAGCAUUGAUAGUUUCAUUAGCUGUGCCACAGACUUCCCUGAGGCCACCAGAUUCUCCCACAGCCCUUUGACAUCACUCCCCAGCAAGACUGGGGGCAGCACAGCCCCAGAAGUGGGCUGGCGGGGAGCUCUGGGUGCCAGUGGUGGUAGGUUUGUGGAGGCCAACCCCAGCCCUGAUGCCAGCCAGCACUCUAGUUUCUUCAUCGAGAGCCCCAAGAGUUCCAUGAAAACUAACAACCCUUUGAAGCUCCGAGCACUUAAAGUCAACUUCAUGGAGGGUGACCCCAGUCCACUCCUCCCCGUUCUAGGGAUGUACCAUGACCCUCUCAGGAACCGGGGGAGUGCUGCGGCUGCUGUCGCUGGACUGGAGUGUGCCACGCUUUUGGACAAGGCUGUGCUGAGCCCAGAGUCCUCCAUCUACACCACAGCAAGUGCUAAGACACCCCCCCGGUCUCCUGAGAAACACACAGCAAUAGCGUUCAACUUUGAGGCGGGUGUCCACCAGUACAUUGACGCAGACACAGAUGAUGAGGGACAGCUGCUCUACAGUGUGGACUCCAGCCCCCCCAAAAGCCUCCCUGGGAGCACCAGUCCGAAGUUCAGCACGGGGACAAGAUCGGAGAAAAACCACUUUGAAAGCUCCCCUUUACCCACCUCCCCUAAGUUCUUAAGGCAGAACUGUAUUUACUCCACAGAAGCAUUGACUGGAAAAGGCCCCAGUGGUCAGGAAAAGUGCAAACUUGAGAACCACAUCUCCCCUGACGUCCGUGUGUUGCCAGGGGGAGGAGCCCAUGGAAGCACACGAGAUCAGAGCAUCUGAACUGCCCUGCCUUGGAGGAGAGACUUUUGGGUGAGGUCCAAAGAGGAGAGCUGUUCAGCUUACCUGCCACAGAGCUUUUCUGCAUGAACUCUGGAACAGAAAGGCCCUGUAAAGCCCUCAGAGAGAAGAGAGACUCCAGAGAAGGCUCCCUAAGACCUUGAGAGCCAUGACAGGUCCAUCAGCAUGAAGUUGGCCAAGCCAUAGGGCACAGCACCUCCUUGUAACAACUCUAUAGCCCUCUUUGGGAGAUGACAUGAGUGGAACUCACAGCCACCACUACCACCACUUUAGACAGGACCGAGGCCACAUACUCCCCAUUCUCUCGUGGCUUUCCAUCUCAGCCUCGGAGGGCAACAUUGACAGUCCUCCUGGCUUCAGCUAGAGAAGGAUGCUGGAACAAGCGGCUGGUGUUGAAAGAGUGGGUUGACCAAUUUGGUAUUGAAUGUUGCCCAGCCACCCCUAGGAACACCUGUCCAUCACCUCCUGGAUGGAUUCCACUGUUAGACAGCUACAGGGAAUGAUUGGUCAUGGGGAAGUCUCUGCGCCAUAAGCCACGAUCCCAGCGCAAAACCCUUACUCAAAUGUCUUCAUUGACUUCGGUAUUUCAUAGUACCUGAGAUUUUAUUUUGAGAUACCAUCAGGGUGAGUUGCACCACUUGUACUCAAUUCUAAUUGCCCCCUGGCAAUCUGGGAAGGGUUCAGAAGGUGGGCACCCAGCCAACAGCAUGAACUCAGAGCAUUGUUUUAGGGUUGGAGGAGGAACACGCUUUCUUUACAUCACUAGUGUAGACUCAAAAGAUAUGCAAGUGUCAAAUAUGCAAAAGAAAUAGUUUAUUCAAAGAGACUGUGUGUUACUGAAGAACAGCAUAAAAAUAUGAUUUUUUUACUUGCAAAAAUGAAAGGAAAAAAAUACCACGCAUUGAAAUGCCCAGUUCAGACUGAAUAAUUCCUGCUGCAGCAAGGAAAGUACCUACUAUAAUAGAAAUUCUGUUUUGUUUUCUGUGGUUUUCAAGUUAAAAAAAAAAAAGUUAAAAUAAAAAGCACUUUAUGUUUUUCAAAAAUAGGUUCUGCCAGGGACAGUGUCAACAUCUUGCACUUUAAAAUAAGCACUAUUUCCCAUAGCCCAAUUGUUGGGACUGUAGUUGGAUUGUUGCUACCUGCCCAUUUCUGGCCAGCAUGGGUAAUAUUGUGCUGGUAUUACUGUCUGCCAUAUCAAAGUCUGUGGGCUCCUUCCCUGCCCCUCUGAAACCUUCCCUUAACCCUCAUGGGUCAGGAGGGGUUCUUGCCCCUUGGGUGGGGCCUCUCAUGAAGUCAAGUAUACAGGAGACAUGCACAUCUCAAAAGGACACAGUGACAGUUGGACAUUGGGUGUUUUACUCUGUUCUCUUUCUUGUCAACCAGCUAUUGGUUUUUCAGUGUCACUGUCUGUACUAAAAGCUCAACUCUCCUUCCUGCAGCCAUCGAUGCAGCCAGUACAGACAAAAGCAAUAAGUAUUUGUGUGCAUCCUGAGUGGUUCUGGUGUAUUUCUUGGUGUUGGUUUUCCUGUCCUCGUUUGAUGACCUGGCAUUGUCCUGCCUGCUUUUAGUCCAACAGCAUGGUGUUGUUGGCCAUUCCUCAGUACAGUGGCAUUAGGUUGAACCACUGAUGAAUACAAUGCUAUAGUGUUGGCUCACCUGUCAGUAAAGAUGACAUGUUAUUGGUCUGCCUGUCUGUAGUACAAUGGAACAAUGUUGUUCUCUUAAUGUAAUGUUGAUGGAUGAUGUCCCAAGUACAAUAGUGUAGUUCUGUCUAUCCUCAAUACAGUAACAGGCAUAUGUCUUCCCAGUGGAAGAAAGAUAUGGUAUUGGUUCACCUAGUCUUAAGUCUCAAUAUCAUCUGUUGCUGGUCUGCCUGUUAGUACAAUGGCAUGAUCCACCUCUCAGUACACAAAUAUCAUGGAGCUGUUCUGCCUGCUCUUCAUACAUAAGGCAUAAGGUUGAGCCACCUGCCACACAUAUGAUGAGAUGGGAUCAUUCCACCACCCUUAAAAAUAUGUCUUCUCUGCUGUAUACAAACCCAAUUCAUAACACUUCUCAGCAUCUCCAGAGACUGUAGAUCCCCCCAAGAGGGUGCAGUCCUGUUCUUUGCCGCAUUAACAGAGAAAACGAGAACGUCACUCUUCCUAGGUAUCUUCAGAGUAUUCGCGCAGCAACUGCAAAGGGACUUAGGGGCAGGGAGAGUGUGAGGUCAUCCCGUGCCAGGCAGAGGAAGCAGCACUCCCAAAACACUUUGCUGAACACGCAGUCUGAGCUGGGGGCCUCUUGAGGAAUGACUGUGGGACAGUUCUCCGCCGACCAUCUCACAUGUCUCUUCUUUGUUUUCAUCACCAUUAAUGUCCACCAUCAGCACAAAUGUGAAAAUUCAGGGAAAAAAACAAAUGCUUUUUGAUAAAAGUAAAUAGUUGUGAUUUCCAAUUCAGAUAUUUUUAGAGCUGAUGCUAUCUGUAAAAAAUAAUAAUAAUAAUAAUAUAGUCUAUUUUACAUAUCAGGAAAGUGAACAUGUUUCAAUAUAGCCAUAUAUAUUGAGAAGGAACUUACCACCCCUUCUUCCAAUCGAGGCAUUUCAUUUGUUGGUUGAAGCAGAUGAGAACUGUACAGAUUGAAAAUGAUUUGUUUUUUUUUUUUUUUAAAAAAAACGAAAACCAAUUGGUGCAACUCUCCUUGUAACCAAAGGCCCUUUCUGCCUUCUGUGGUCAUGUAGGACCUGGCCCUUCCUUCCUUGUGUAUUUUGUCCAACCGUAAAGUAGCAUUUUAUUGAGUCACUUUUGAAGGACGAAUUCAGAAGUAUCAUUAAGAACCUACCUUUUCAGGCUUCAUAGCCAGAGUCCUAUAGAGUUCUUAUAGAAACAGAAUAAUUGAAAUUCAGCAUAUACUAUGCUUAGAAAGUAUUUUGUUUGGGUUUGAUUGGGUUUUUUUUUCUUUUACUUGUGUGUGUAUGUACUGGGGGAGUAUAGCUUUUAUUCUGUGCUCAAUUCGAAAGAGAGUAUUAUAAGUUUUCCCAGCCCAUCCACCCGCUAAAAAAGAACAUAUCCAAAUUUUAAUAUGUAUACACCCAACCUGUACCUAUGUACGUGAAUAUACAUGCACUGGGAAAUCUACUUAAGAGUCUUCACUGAGAAGUUCACUCGAUAGAAAGGUCUUGAUAGAGAAGAGAAGAGGAAAGCAAUGGUCUGAAGGCAAAUCCUGCUUUAACUUGGUGGUCCAUUUCCCAUUCAUUCCUGAACCAAUGAGAGCAGAAAGAAACAAGUCAACCCAAACAAGCAAACUAGGGGCUGGACGCGGCGAAUGGAUGCUGGUCAGUUUGGCAAAUUCACUGAAACUCAUCAAGAACCCAGCUGAACUUGCAUUCCAACUUCCACAAUUAUCUGAAAGGGCUAGGGACCAGGUAGCCAUGUGUCCCAAUCACACGGGGGAGAGUCUGCCACCGGCGGUGAGAGAGGUGGGGAAGCUUUGGAGGAGACAGUAUAUUCACCUUUUUAUCUUUGGGUAAAAGAAACCAACAGGACUUUGGUGCAGUAGAUUUCUCAGUGCCUUCUUUAGGAAUUCUAUCUUAAGCACACUUCAAGGGGAAAGAAAAAAGGAGGAGAGAACAUUUGUUCCCGUGAAGUCCCUUUCUCCAAAGGACUGGGGAUCAAGAAGGAAGAAGAGUAAGAAGGAAAAACAACAAAAUCCUGAGGAGGCCAUUUCUUUUAACCCACCCAGCUUGCCCCUGAAAACUGCUGGUGAUACAAACUUUUUCAAACUGACUUCCAGCUUCUCCAUGUGUCUUGGUAACUGUAGCCUCGUCUCUGCCCUUUCUCCUAAUAAGAUCCAUGUUUCUAAGGAGAAAAACAAAACAGUAUUCUCUUCUGUAAAACUGUAAUGUAUUGUUGAUAUUUGUAACUAUUGUAUAUUUCUGUCUUGCUCCAGUCCCAGCUGGAGUGUCUAGUUCCAUGGACAAGGGGAUAUUUAAAAUUCACCACGGACAAGAGCCACUAAAGCCAGGUCUCUAUCGCUAAUCUCUCUCCUAUUCUUAUUUCUCUACCAACUAAUCUCAAGUAACAAUACCCCAGGCUUUUUUUCAGCCUCAAUUCAAGUAACUUUGAAUCAAAAGAGAGCAAGGCAAAAAGCCUCCGGACAUGCUUCUUUGGGAAAGGACUUUUUCUGUAGCUGCAGAGUGGGCAGGAGGGAGAAGGGGCUCCCCUGAGACCCCGGCAGGACAAUGGAAAGCUUCCAGCCCCGAGCUGAUGUUUCCUCACCUAUCACUGCUUAUAGGACAGCAUCCAAAUGCUUUCAUGUCACUCAGCCCAGGCAACCCAAACCAGUCCUGGCUACACCCAGAAAUAAGAGUUACCUCUGCAUUUUCUGUUGCCAUUUUUCUGGCUCUAGAAGUAUCUGAUGCGCGACUAUGUCAUAGAAUGUCCACGCAUCUCAGAGUAGUCUAUUUUUCUGUUCAGAUAAAAUAUAUAUAUAUAUGUAUUUUUAGCAAAUUUAUAAUAGGGCAAUUGAGUCUAAUUUCUUCUUUUGUAAUACAGAACAAUAUCUUAGGAGUUUCAUUGUUGGUCAUUAUCGUAGCUGAUGUUUUCUGGUCUUUUGCAGUUCCUACCAUUGUCCCUUGGGCUGUUUGGGUUUUCUUCCUUUUGAUUCUGAUUUCUUGAGGGUGGGGAAAGACUUUGGGGUUUGACUUCCUUGUGUAGGCAUUUCUUGACACUAGGCCUGGACUCUGUCAAUGCUGUGACUUUCCUCAUUCAUUUCUGUGUGUUUCUCCCAUUCGUUGUUCUUAAGAAUCCAGGGCAUGAAUGCAGGAAUGAGACCCAGGGAAGCAGAGCUACAGAUGGCCCUCAAAAUCAGGAUGGGAUGUGGGCUGGUUUCACUUAUAUCCCACACCCCUUUAGGGAUCUGAAGGGACUGAGUUUUCUCAUCCCCAGAGAUCUUGGAACCAAAAAUCUCAUGCAAGCAAACUCAUCACUGGCAUUUCUGAGAUCCAGAACACAUGUGAGUCCCUCCUGGCUGGGCUGCUCCCACAUGUCCAGCACCCUGUCGGCCUGUAACAUCAAUCAGAGCUGAAGGUCAGAGGUUUUUCAGGUUCUCGUGAACCUCACAAGAACAUGCUGGGCCUCCGAUCUCACCAACUUGUUUAUCAGUUCCUUGUUUCGAUCUGUUUAUUUAUUUAUUUUUUUGUUAUUAUUAUUUUGAGACAAAGUCUUGCUCUGUUGCCCAGGCUGCAGUGCAAUGGCGCAAUCUCGGCUCACUGCAACCUCCUCCACCCAGGUUCAAGUGAUUCUCAUGUCUCAGCCUCCUGAGUAACUGGGAUUACAAGAGCGCACCAUCACGCCCAGCUAAUUUUUGUAUUUUUAGUAGAGGCAGAGUUUCUCCAUGUUGGCCAGGCUGGUCUUGAACUCCUGACCUCAGGUGAUCUGCCUGCCUCGGCCUCCCAGUGCUAGGAUUACAGGUGUGAGCCACCACUGCACCCAGUCCAUUUCAAUCCAUUUCUAACAGCUUCACCAAAAAACAGUGGCCAGACACCCUUGCAGCCAAACCCUGAGAAGAGAUGUCCCCGAAUCUGCUAGCUCAUCUCCCCUUCCCUUGCCAGCUGCCUGGCUCCAUAGAGCAGGAGGUGUGUGGCAAGGACAGGGGCAGUUUUCCAGCUUCCACCUAUCCACGCCUGGGGGAGUUUUUGGACUGUCCUGAUAAUUAAUUCCAGAGGCAGUUUUCAGUCCUGGGUGGGCGGAGGACAUCUCACUAGGCAGGAUCUUCAGCAGAAAGUGAUUCUCCAUCCGUCAACUCAUGCAGGAAGAUGAAGAAAGCCCAGAUAAUCUCCAACUUGCAUUCGUUUAGGUUUUGGUAUACCACCCACCUCACUGUCAGCUGCAGGGCUUGGGGCUCUGCCUAGAAUCAGAAAUUUGAGCCAAACUGGGACCCUCAGAUGGCAGUGAGCCAUCCCAUCAGAUAACUCCCAAGAGGAAGCCAACUCAAAUAUGAAUUUUAUUAUUCUGGACUAUGACCCUGAUCAGAGUUCUCCCACCCCGAAAACCUCUGAUAGUCUGGUUUGAACCAGAGUCAAAUAAAACAGACAAGAUUUUUUUUUCCUCUGCACAAAAGCAAAAAAACAAAACAAAAAAAAGUCUGCCAGUAGUUUCCUGGGUUUGAUGCCCAGAUAAGCAAACACUGUUGCCUAUGGCUGUUGCUGUUUUCAUCAAGAAAGAGGUUAUAUAGUUUGCAUUUCCAUCCACUCUCCCUGAUUUUAUCUUAACCUAGAAUUUCUCCUGAACUACCCCAAAUGCCAACUUGAAUUUGGGUAGGGCUCUGUUAAUCGAGGGAACCCUCAUCUUCACUUAUAAACCUAAUUCUCUGUUCCUCCCUCCAAAGAUCCUGAAAAGAUCUCCUAAAGGCUGGCCAGGAUGGGGUGGAGUGGGGCAGUGCACCUGAAGAAAAAAACUUAGCUGCCAGCUGGCUGUAUGCAAGUUCUCCGAAAAUUUCUAUUGUAUGAAAGGGAUGGGGUCAAUUGCAGCUCAAAUUAAGGAAGCCCUCCUAACAGGCUGGGUUGUCUGACCAUGGAGCUCAAUGCCAUGGUGGACAGUGAGCUCCCUUAUAUCACAGGUGUUUAAAGAGAGGCUGGCUAGAUGGUGUAAAAAAUGGGCAUUGCAGAGGGGCCCUAGCAUUGCAUGGAAACUGGGCUGAACAACCACAGAAAUUCCUCUUUGUUUCUUGGAGUGUGUGUGUGUGUGUGUGUGUGUGUGUGUGUGUGUGUGUGUGUAGGUGGUUUCAACACUCUGGAUAUAAGCUCAAGCCACUGAGGCAAAGGCAUGCAGCACAAUUAGCAGGAAUGCAACUUCUGGGCUUUGGAGCUCUCAGAGGGGGUGUCCAAGAGACAAGUCUGCUUCCUUCCGGCUCCGUCUUGGAACAUUUUAAUGACUGUCAGUCACCAAUCCAACCCAUCCCCAGUGGCCUACCAGGCACCACAUUGGGAUGAGACUCAUGCUACCCUUCCCCAGGCCAGCCAAGGAGCAAUCCACGCUGUCCCCCAUCCCUGGCUGGCUGUCUUAUGGUGCUUCAGCCCCUCCGCCCAGCUCCUGUGCCCUCAUGAGCCUGGGGCUUUCUGUAUAAAAGAUGCAAUGAUAUCUGUUCCCCACUAGCCAUCCCCACAAUGAACAACUUCCCAGGCAAUAGCAAAUGGCUCCAUUCCAAAAGGGCUUGUUUUUUUGGUAAAUCAAAUAAGAGACCCCACUCAAGACCUUUGAAAGUCCCCGUCAAUGAAAAAAAUCCAGAAGGGUCAAAAGAGAAAGGCAGCUUUUAAUCCAGUUUCACAGCAAAACCAGGCUCUUGGCUGCCUCCAAGCAGAAUGCCACUCUCCUGCAGCUGUGGCCUCCAUCCCAAAUCAUCCUGCAUACUGCAUUCUCUAAGGAAAGCAUUUGACAAGAGAGGGUUUAUGUAUGGUGGAUUGGGAGAAAGUGAGACUUCAACCUCAGGGUGAACCGAAGACUGGUUUGUCUUUGGUUGUUUUAGUAUGAGGUUGGGCAGGAUGAUAUGUUUGGAUGGGUAGAAUGAGCAGCCGCCUUCCUCUGAAACCAAAAUAAAAUAAAAACCAGUUUUCAAGAUUCCUCCCAACUCCUCACUGGAGGCUCUGCCCUGCAGAAUCACUCAAGUUGCAACAACACAAGGAGACAAAAAUAGGAUAUUUCAUGAAAAUAUAAGAAACUCCCAAUUCCGUCCCAUUAGGAUGCCCUCAAGGGGCCAUGCAGGGAUCUUCCCAUACUUCCUGCUUCCCUGAUCUGAACCAAGAUUGGAAAGAGGCAGGCAGCAGAGAAGAUGCCCAAGAAACUCUGACAUAUCCACAGCUUGGCUCUGCCCCUUGGGCUUCACUGGGGUUUGGGCCUCCCUCUUGGUUGAGCUGAGUGUGCCUGAGUGGGUGGGGACAGGGAGGAUUCUCCAGGUCUAUCUUGAUUUCAUAGGUCCUUCUCAAUCCAAGGUCAAAAACUGAGAAUCUUAUUUUCUGCACCAGGAACUCAGGGUUAUCCCCAACCUAUGCCGCUGGCACAUGAUGGUCAUCCAACCUGUGUUUUUGUGAGUGAGUGAAUGUGUGACUGGUUGGCCUCUGAGUGGAUGACUGGAUGCGUGAAUGUGUGAGUGAAUGGGGGAGUUAAUGAAUCCCUACCUAACUGUGAAGAGAAGAAAAAUGAGGAGCCCCUCUCCCACUGAAACCCAUAACUGCCCCAUCAAGGUCAUCUUUCUUUGACUCAAGAUGACAUCUCAAUUUGAUGCUUGUAGGCCCCAAGCUGAUAAGGGCCACAGCCCUCUCAGAGCCACACUUCCUGGGGGCCCACAGAGCAGCUCUGCCCUCCUUCCUCUUCCCCUACCCUGCAUUUCUCAGCCUCAUGUUCUAUUUUAGCUCACACACGACCCAUGGGGGGGACCACCAAGUGGUUUUCCAAUGGACUAAGCCAAGGGUUCGAAGUUGGGACUUCCUUUGGUCUGGGACUUCCUGGGGCAGAAACAUAGGAGCCAACAUCUGGAAACUGGAUUGCAUUCCCUGAGCCAUGGGAGUCCAGCUGGAUAUUAAGGCCAGCCUGCCCUCCAGCUUUUAGAGCCGAAGAUCUUUUUUUCUGAGCCCCAAAGCCGUCAUGAUAGUAUGCCCCCAGAUCCCAUCAGCUAAGACCCUGUCUCUCCCAGGAACCCGUCGUGUGAGGUUGGGGCUUUUCUGCCAGUAAAGCCAUUCUGAUCACCUCACCCUUGACAGGGGCCAAGCCAAUCACAUUAGCCAUAAAUGACCAAUGUCCUCAGCCACUCUUUUCUCGGGGGUGCAUUCGUGGGUCCUAUUCAUCUCUCGUCAGUUAAUGUCUCUAGUCCUUCCUGUAAAGGUGAAAAUAAGCAUUGCGCAUGUGCGCAACACACACGCACACACACACACACACACACACACACAAAUCCCAGUGUCUUUUUAUGCAUGUGGUGAGAUGAAAUUGUGAUCUUUGUGUGACCUCCAGCUGCUGUCUUGUCUUGUAAAAUAUGUCCAAAUGUUUAAGAAUUUCUAAGCAAAUGGUCCCUUAAUGAAGUCUGCAGAGUUCAAUAAAAGGUAUGGAAAAAACAA